AGGGGAAGCUGCAUGACCCCCAGCUCAUGGGGAUCAUCCCACGAAUUGCCCAUGAUAUCUUUGACCAUAUCUACUCCAUGGAUGAGAACCUGGAGUUUCACAUAAAGGUUUCCUAUUUUGAGAUCUACUUGGACAAAAUAAGGGACUUACUUGAUGUAUCCAAGACCAACUUGGCUGUUCAUGAAGAUAAAAACAGAGUCCCGUAUGUAAAGGGGUGCACUGAGCGGUUUGUGUCGAGCCCUGAGGAAGUCAUGGAUGUAAUAGAUGAAGGCAAAGCAAACCGACACGUGGCUGUGACAAACAUGAAUGAACACAGCUCUAGAAGUCACAGUAUCUUCCUGAUAAAUAUUAAACAAGAGAAUGUAGAGACUGAAAAAAAACUCAGUGGGAAACUUUAUUUGGUUGAUUUGGCUGGGAGCGAAAAGGUCAGCAAAACUGGUGCCGAGGGAGCUGUUCUUGACGAAGCUAAAAAUAUCAAUAAGUCUUUGUCUGCUCUUGGAAAUGUGAUCUCUGCUUUGGCAGAAGGGACAAAAACACAUGUGCCAUACCGGGACAGCAAGAUGACUCGGAUUCUUCAGGACUCUUUGGGUGGGAACUGCAGAACCACCAUCGUCAUUUGCUGUUCUCCUUCUGUCUUCAAUGAGGCUGAGACCAAGUCCACACUGAUGUUCGGACAGAGAGCUAAGACCAUCAAGAAUACAGUCUCUGUGAACCUAGAACUGACAGCAGAAGAAUGGAAGAAGAAAUAUGAAAAAGAGAAAGAGAAAAACAAGACUUUGAAGAAUGUUAUCCAGCAUCUGGAGAUGGAGCUAAACAGGUGGAGGAAUGGAGAAGCUGUGCCUGAGGAUGAACAGAUCAGUGCCAAGGACCAGAAGAACCUGGAGCCUUGUGAUAACACCCCCAUCAUAGACAAUAUUGCUCCUGUUGUUGCUGGCAUCUCUACAGAGGAGAAAGAGAAGUACGAUGAGGAGAUCUCCAGUCUCUACAGACAACUGGAUGACAAGGAUGAUGAAAUUAACCAGCAGAGCCAGCUGGCUGAAAAGCUGAAGCAACAGAUGUUGGAUCAGGAUGAGCUUUUAGCUUCCACAAGAAGAGACUAUGAGAAGAUACAGGAGGAGCUGACACGUCUCCAGAUUGAAAAUGAGGCAGCCAAGGAUGAGGUGAAAGAAGUUCUCCAGGCCCUGGAGGAGCUGGCUGUCAAUUAUGACCAGAAAUCACAGGAAGUGGAGGAUAAGACCCGGGCCAAUGAGCAGCUGACAGACGAGCUGGCCCAGAAAACGACUACAUUGACAACCACACAGAGAGAGCUGAGCCAGCUACAAGAGCUUAGCAACCACCAGAAGAAAAGGGCAACUGAGAUCCUGAAUUUGCUGUUGAAAGAUCUGGGGGAGAUAGGUGGAAUUAUUGGCACCAAUGAUGUGAAAACUUUGGCAGAUGUGAAUGGAGUCAUUGAGGAGGAGUUUACCAUGGCCCGCCUGUACAUCAGCAAGAUGAAGUCAGAGGUCAAGUCCCUGGUGAACCGCAGCAAACAGCUCGAGAGCGCCCAGAUGGACUCCAACAGGAAGAUGAAUGCCAGCGAGCGGGAGCUGGCAGCCUGCCAGCUGCUCAUCUCCCAGCACGAAGCCAAGAUCAAGUCUCUGACAGACUACAUGCAGAACAUGGAACAGAAGAGGAGGCAGCUAGAAGAGUCCCAGGACUCGCUCAGCGAAGAGCUGGCAAAGCUCCGAGCCCAGGAAAAAAUGCACGAAGUCAGCUUCCAGGAUAAGGAGAAGGAACAUCUGACGCGGUUGCAGGAUGCUGAAGAAAUGAAGAAGGCGCUGGAGCAGCAGAUGGAGAGCCACCGGGAAGCUCACCAGAAGCAGCUGUCCAGACUCCGAGACGAAAUUGAGGAGAAGCAGAAAAUCAUUGAUGAGAUUCGGGAUUUGAAUCAGAAACUGCAACUGGAACAGGAGAAGCUUAGUUCUGAUUAUAACAAGCUGAAAAUAGAGGACCAAGAGAGAGAAAUGAAGCUGGAAAAGCUCUUAUUGCUCAACGAUAAAAGGGAACAAGCCAGAGAAGACCUCAAAGGGCUGGAGGAGACAGUGUCUAGAGAAUUGCAGACACUGCACAACCUUCGGAAACUCUUUGUCCAGGAUCUGACCACCCGAGUUAAAAAAAGUGUGGAGUUGGACAACGAUGAUGGAGGGGGCAGUGCUGCCCAGAAGCAGAAAAUUUCCUUCUUGGAGAAUAACCUGGAGCAGCUCACCAAAGUUCACAAGCAGCUGGUCCGGGACAACGCAGACCUGCGCUGUGAACUGCCCAAGCUGGAGAAGCGGCUGCGUGCCACGGCGGAGCGCGUCAAGGCUCUGGAGAGCGCGCUGAAGGAGGCCAAGGAGAACGCCAUGCGGGACCGUAAGCGCUACCAGCAGGAGGUGGAUCGUAUCAAGGAGGCCGUGCGGGCCAAGAACAUGGCCAGAAGGGCCCAUUCAGCCCAGAUCGCCAAGCCCAUCCGCCCCGGACACUACCCGGCCUCAUCUCCAACGGCCGUCCAUGCCAUUCGAGGGGGAGGAGGCAGCUCUUCAAAUUCCACUCACUACCAGAAAUAAAUACAAAAUAUGACUCCACGUAGCAUGUCAAGGACUACAUUAAUCACCAAUUCCUUUAUUUUUCCCCCCCUACAGUUUCCAUUUUUUUUUUAUACUUGCUUACUCCAGCCAUCUGCAGUACACCAGUUUCAGGUCUUUUGAGCUGUGUAGAGUUUCUGUGUGUACAGAUGUGUGCUCGGACUUUUCUCUUUUUGAGAAAUCUGAAGGAGAUGGUUGCAGAAGAUCCACUUACUACUGAGAACCAUUACCACCGACUCGGCCUCCGGGGUGUUGGGUGGUUUCUGGGUGGUUCCUGGAGCCUCCUCUGGGCAGUGCACUGUCCCAUCUGUACGCCCUAAUGUGCCAUUCCCUAGAGGGGAACAACCAAGUGCCGUGGAGGCAGAUGAUCAUGGUCUGCCUCAACUGUCUGGUUUCCUGUAAAAUAAACACAUUGUUUUAUAUUUUUAGGGAACAAAAAGUGCUGCUAUAGGGUUCAAAGUUUUCCUUCUGAACACUUUUCCGAAACAAAUUACCCCAAAGACACAUUUUGAAUAUCCUGGUCACAUCUUUGGAUCUGUAAAAUAUACCUUUUAGUAUGGCACCUGUUAAAAUGCAAAGCAAAUUUCUUUGGGGCAGAAAAACAAUCUGACAGUAGCAGUGUAGAAUUUGUUCAUUCAAAUACAUCUGUGUAAAUGCAAAAAGUCAUAAAAUUCACCUCCGAGCUGCUUGCUUUUGAACCUGCAGCAACUAGUCUUAGCCGGCCCGGUUUGAACAUCGUUCUUUCAGAAGUGCUGAAAAUGCUGCAAAGUUGGAUAAGUGGAAAUGUGGCUGCCCCUCUCCUCACUACUUCCUCUCUGAUCGUUCUGAAGCUUGCAUUGGGAAUGGCUGCUUUCUCUAACCAUUUUCAGCUUGAGUGGGUAUUGCUGAAGAAAUCCAACAUCAUUCCAGCAGUUGAAAAAGGAAGCCUUCGGGAGAAAGUGCUUGUCAAAAUUUUGUUCUUUGUGCUUGUGUAUGAGUAAGUUGCCAUGAAUAAGUUAUUAUUUUAACCCAUAAUUGGCGACUGUUUAUAU